GCCGGAAGAGUCAGGUUCUGUGUAUGUCUCCGCGUCUUCCGCGGAGCGGGUGUGCAGGGCCUGCAGCAUUGAACUAGAUGUCGUCCCCGCAGGCCCCAGAAGAUGGGCAGGGCUGUGGCGACCGCGGCGAUCCCCCUGGGGACCUCCGUAGCGUCUUGGUCACGACCGUGCUCAACCUCGAGCCGCUGGACGAGGAUCUCUUCAGAGGAAGGCAUUACUGGGUACCGGCCAAGAGGCUGUUUGGUGGUCAGAUCGUGGGCCAGGCCCUGGUGGCUGCAGCCAAGUCUGUGAGUGAAGACGUCCACGUGCACUCCCUGCACUGCUACUUUGUUCGGGCAGGGGACCCGAAGCUGCCAGUACUGUACCAAGUGGAGCGGACACGAACAGGGUCGAGCUUCUCGGUGCGCUCUGUGAAGGCCGUGCAACAUGGGAAGCCCAUCUUCAUCUGCCAGGCCUCCUUCCAGCAGGCCCAGCCCAGCCCCAUGCAGCACCAGUUCUCCAUGCCCACUGUGCCACCACCAGAAGAGCUGCUUGACUGUGAGACCCUCAUUGACCAGUAUUUAAGGGACCCUAACCUCCAAAAGAGGUACCCAUUGGCGCUCAACCGAAUUGCUGCUCAGGAGGUCCCCAUUGAGAUCAAGCCAGUAAACCCAUCCCCCCUGAGCCAGCUGCAGAGAAUGGAGCCCAAACAGAUGUUCUGGGUGCGAGCCCGGGGCUAUAUUGGCGAGGGCGACAUGAAGAUGCACUGCUGCGUGGCCGCCUAUAUCUCCGACUAUGCCUUCUUGGGCACUGCACUGCUGCCUCACCAGUGGCAGCACAAGGUGCACUUCAUGGUCUCACUGGACCAUUCCAUGUGGUUCCACGCCCCCUUCCGAGCUGACCACUGGAUGCUCUAUGAAUGCGAGAGCCCCUGGGCCGGUGGCUCUCGGGGGCUGGUCCAUGGGCGGCUGUGGCGUCAGGAUGGAGUCCUAGCUGUGACCUGUGCCCAGGAGGGCGUGAUCCGAGUGAAGCCCCAGGUCUCAGAGAGCAAGCUGUAGCCAGAGGUACCAGCUUCGCCUGGGGCUUCAAGAACCUCCCAUCUAUCCCCAUUCCUGAGACAGGAGUUACAGUCCCUUUUGGCCCUCACAUCCAAUAAAGAGACUGAUACCACUGGA